ACAGCUUGGGACUGCUGAGGGGCAGGCGGCUGCAGGCUAGGGGCGGCUCGGAGUCCGCUGGCCACCCAGCUGAGAGGAGAGGCGCCCCCGGGGACGCACUGAGAUUAUGAGGCUCUGGCCUCCACUGGCCACUCACUCGUGACCCUUUCCACCACGGCGGAGCCUUCCAAGCCUACCUCCUGCCGUGUGGUGAUCUACCUGCAGCGGGAGAUGUCGGGGGACACCUGCCUGUGCCCAGCCUCAGGGGCCAAGCCCAAGCUCAGUGGCUUCAAGGGAGGAGGGUUGGGCAACAAGUAUGUCCAGCUCAACGUGGGCGGCUCUCUGUACUACACCACUGUGCGGGCCCUGACCCGCCACGACACCAUGCUCAAGGCCAUGUUCAGUGGGCGCAUGGAGGUGCUGACCGACAAAGAAGGCUGGAUCCUCAUAGACCGUUGUGGAAAGCACUUUGGCACCAUUUUGAAUUACCUCCGAGAUGACACCAUCACCCUCCCUCAGAACCGGCAAGAAAUCAAGGAAUUGAUGGCUGAAGCAAAGUAUUACCUCAUCCAGGGGCUGGUGAAUAUGUGCCAGAGUGCCCUGCAGGACAAGAAGGACUCCUACCAGCCUGUGUGCAACAUCCCCAUCAUCACAUCCCUAAAGGAGGAGGAGCGGCUCAUCGAAUCCUCCACCAAGCCCGUGGUGAAGCUGCUGUACAACAGAAGCAACAACAAGUAUUCCUACACCAGCAACUCUGACGACCACCUGCUGAAAAACAUCGAGCUGUUUGACAAGCUCUCCCUGCGCUUCAACGGCCGCGUGCUCUUCAUCAAGGAUGUCAUUGGUGACGAGAUCUGCUGCUGGUCCUUUUAUGGCCAGGGCCGUAAGCUGGCAGAGGUGUGCUGUACCUCCAUCGUGUAUGCCACGGAGAAGAAGCAGACCAAGGUGUGGGGGAUUGCCCCUGCCUGGGUAGGGGAGGACACACACCCACUGUGCGGGGGACGUGGUCGGGCUGUGACCAGCACGGAGCAAAAGGGGCAUGGACUUGGCUCUUUUUUCCAAACACGGUGGAAUUCCCAGAGGCCCGAAUCUAUGAGGAGACACUCAACGUCCUACUCUAUGAGACUCCCCGCGUCCCCGACAACUCCUUGUUGGAGGCCACAAGCCGUAGCCGCAGCCAGGCUUCCCCCAGUGAAGAUGAGGAGACCUUUGAACUGCGGGACCGUGUCCGCCGCAUCCACGUCAAGCGCUACAGCACUUACGAUGACCGGCAGCUCGGCCACCAGUCUACCCAUCGCGACUGACCAGACCCUCAGGGAGUCAGGGCACGGGAGGCCCUAUCUCCCAUCCUGUGGAACCCGCCCCAUUGGCCACCCCAUGCUGCUGCUGCCUGGGUCUCUGCUCUAGCACCCAGAGGCAUGACAGGCCCUGCUCAGAGGUCAGAGGGUCUGGGCAGAGGAGGGACCACAUUCCCCUGCCUUGCCCCUGAGCACUUCUGGAGACUGCGUCCUGUCCUAUCUGCUCACCAUCACCCUUCCUGCCCGACGGAGCUGCUUCUGCUCCCUGGGGCAUAUGGACUGACCCACCUCCUGCUGAGAACCUUCCCCUAGGCCCUGUGCAGAAGGCUACUGCCCCUUAGGCCUCAGCUGGGGGAAAGGCAGUUCUGGUGCUGUAGAGGCCCUGGUGCAGAAAGUGGGACGUCUUUUUUCCUAAGGUGUUUAAGCACAGGCUUGAUAAGUUUGGUUUUUAAAAAAUAAUCUAGGAAAUGAAUAAUUCUAAAUCUAGUAAUGAGGAAACUGAGCAUUUCUUUUGCCCUCCAGGGUGCCAAGACCCUACAUAUGACAGAACCCUUGGCCCUUCUCCAUGCCUGUGGGAUCUGUUUCUUUAAAGCACUUUGUACUGUUAUUCAGGAGGUUGAUAAUCUCCUUGACCCAUGUCUUUCUACCCUAAUCCCCACUUCCCUGCAGAAUCAAUCUGAGGGAGGGGAUAAAGAGGAAGCAAUAAAAAAAAAACAUCCGACAGAGCAGCUCUGGCUUUGCAGCCUGGCCAGCAGCUCAGAGUGCACCGAGGAGGGAAGGAUGGCUAAGCUGGGACCGGCAGUCCUCACAGGGUGCCUGUGAGAAAGGACAUUUUACCCCCACAUCAUAGUCACAUCACUGACUCCUAGGUCUAGCACGACUGCUCUUUGUGAUUCUCUUGAGUACCCUUGGCUUCCAGCCAUGCUGUCCUCACAUACGGUAAAGCCAAAGAGCUGUCACAUGGGCCAGAAACAUGAGCCACGGCAGGAAGACCGUGGAGCCCGUGGGCACUGCAUGGUGUUGGCUGGCAUGCCCAUCAGCUGAGGACAGCAAACUCCCAGCAGCCCCUACAGAGGUGGCACAUGCUUGGCCACACAUCUACUCCCUGCCCACACCAUCUAUGCUCUUGGUUGGUGCUGGCUGGGAUGGCGGUUCUGCCCAGUGGUGUCUCUGAGCGCGGGAUGACAGGAGCAACCGAAGCACCCUGAAGGCCUUCACUCCUUGUUGGGUAACUCAGCCAUGGAGAUGCCAAGCACUAGCCAGGAGGUGAGUUCCUCUUUAGGGCUUUGGUUUUCAUUCCUUUUUGUUUGGCUUGGCCAAACCAGAAUUCAGCUUAUCUGAAUUAUUUUCCAAAGGAAUGCUGUCAGGGAGGGACUGUUCUGCCAGCCUAACAAAGCAACGUAGCCACGUAUAGUACCCACUUUCUGCUCUUUGGAGAGAACACAGGUUAUCAAGUUCAUCUCUCUUGACUACUCUUAUGAUAGCUGAUGCCACAGAGCCUAUGGGCAAAUGCCAGACCCAGGGUUAGACACAAGGACCUGAAGUGACAUGACGGCGGGACAGGGGAAAUGUGACUUUCUAAUUAGGCAUUUUAUGUUAGUCACAGUCUUGAAUGUAUAAACAGCACUAAGACUCUCAGGUCAGGUACCUUGGUGAUCAGCUACUAGUUCUUCCAGCCCUCAUUGAGGUAACAAGAUAAAGACAAAUCCACUUCUUUGGCCAAAUUCAGGCUUUGGCUUUAUGACUUUCCCACAGAGACUGGAAUGCGUCAGCCUGAGACCACUGGCCUAUUUUCUCAGCUGCCCUCUUGAGGUCCUUUAACACUCAAAUUCCCAGCUCCCCACUGAGGUGUUGUGAUGCUUGCCUUUUGACCUCCCCAUCCCCUUUAGUCCCUGCUUACUACUUUGACAUUCACAUCCUCAGUGUCUCAGUCUUUUUUGCCGAGAAAGCACAGUAGUCUGGGACUGGGCAUUUAUCUUCUCUGACUGAAAAUCUCUCCUUGGUCUUAAGGAAAAUACUAACAUUGAACUCACUGACAUGAUCUUAGCUUCUUUAAUCAGACUUUGUGACUUAAAAGUUUGGGGGUUUUCUUUGAAAGUUUCCAGCCCUAUUCAGAAAGCAACUCUUGGCUGUGUGCAUUUUUCAACUCCAAGCAGCCCAGGGGUAAGUAAACAAAGUAUGGAUGAAGGUCAGAUUUUCUUGUCAGUUUCUGAGAAACCUGGCAGCCUGCUGUUAACAACACAGGCCAGUAUUGGGUUUUAUUGAAUUUGGUAUGUGACCAAGGUCGGCCUAAAGGAUGGCGCAGGUCCUGGGCAGGAAAGAAUUUUUCCUUUAUCACAUAACUGUAAUAUUUGGUUGCUCAGCAUAAGUGAUGGAAGCAAACACUAAUUUCUAAUAAAAUUGUGUUAAACUCAA